GCACUGCGUCUCCCAAGGUGGCUGAAGCUGGCCAGCUGCGGGCUCCGCGCCGCUCGUCCCGGGUCUAUGGGUCCAUUCCCCACGCCCACCCGGACCCCGGGGUCACUCGGGUCUCCGUCUGUGCCAGGGAGGGAGAAUCACGCCCAGGGUCCUCUCUGGCUUCGCGCGACUGAGAACGCGCCCGGACGCGGCGCGGCGCUCCUGAGUCAAAGGAGAGGUGGCGGCAGGACCACCCCAGGGCGCCGUCUGCACCCCCGGACGCACUCGGCCGUGCUGCGCUUCCGGGACAAGGCGUCGGUUCUCGCCUGAGGGCCAAACCUUGCCCCUGCCCACCUUCCUCACCCCCGCCAUUUCCAGGACUCACAUCCAAAGGCGACAGCACCAGGAUUUGCUCCCGCCUUUGGCACAGAGGAGGACGGGUCCCUCUCUCAGCCUGGCCAGUCUUUCCCAGGGCUUGAUGGGAAAAAGGACUUCCCUAGAAGUGAGUCUUGGGGAGUUGGGGGGAGAAAAGUGUCGAGGAGGGCGUCGGAGUUUCCCACCGCUGGCUGCUUCCCGGCCCGCACGCCCGGGAGGGUGGCGGUGGGCGCGCAGAGAUCUUUGCAAAACAGCGUCCAGGGCGGAAAACAACUCACAGGCCUGCCGCCCCCAAAGGCGGGCAGGUCCGGACGCGCUGGGCCCUGGUCCCUUCGGCCGCAAACGGCGCAAGUCACGCACUGCGUUCACCGCGCAACAGGUGCUGGAGCUGGAGCGGCGCUUCGUCUUCCAGAAGUACCUGGCGCCGUCCGAGCGAGACGGGCUAGCUACGCGACUCGGCCUGGCCAACGCGCAGGUGGUCACUUGGUUCCAGAACCGGCGAGCCAAGCUCAAGCGCGAUGUGGAGGAGAUGCGCGCCGACGUCGCCUCGCUACGCGCGUUGUCCCCGGAAGUCCUGUGCAGCUUAGCACUGCCCGAAGGCGCUCCAGAUCCCGGCCUCUGCCUCGGCCCUGCCGGCCCUGACUCCCGGCCCCACCUGUCAGACGAGGAGAUACAGGUGGACGAUUGAAGACAAAGCCGCCGCCAAUCCUGGGCUCUGGGGCCCUGGACUCCUCACCUCGCGCUCUGCCUCUGGCCAGAGUUCCAGGGUGGAGGAAGGAGGUCCACUUGGGCCUCUUCCGGCCCACAGUCCAGACGCUCACCUUUCCCGGUUUUUUUGUAAGUUUGUUUUGUUGUCUGAGACAGGGCCUCGCUCUGUCGCCCAGGCUGGAGUGCCGUGGAGCGAUCACCGCUCACUGCAGUCGCGACCUCCUGGGCUCAAGCGAUCCUCCUGCCUCAACCUCCCGACUAGCUGGCAUUACAGGCGUGCAGCACCACCCCAGGCUAAUUUAAAAAACUUUUUUUUUUAGAGAGGAGGUCCCGCUAUGUUGUCCAGGCUACUUUCCCAAUAUUUGAGAAUAAAGUCGAGACUCUGCCGCA